AGCCCGUUCCUGCUCCGCGCUUCUGGAGCACUGGCCAAGGCGGGCCGAUUCAGGACCCAGGUUACUUGGGCGGCGAGCUGGACUGUUUCUACUCCUCCCUCCUCCUCCACUGCGGGGUCUGACCCUACUCCUUGUGUGAGGACUCCUCUAGUUCAGAGACAUAUUCUGUUCACCAAACUUGACUGCGCUCUAUCGAGGUCGUUAAAUUCUUCGGAAAUGCCUCACAUAUAGUUUGGCAGCUAGCCCUUGCCCUGUUGGAUGAAUAGGCACCUCUGGAAGAGCCAACUGUGUGAGAUGGUGCAGCCCAGUGGUGGCCCGGCAGCAGAUCAGGACGUACUGGGCGAAGAGUCUCCUCUGGGGAAGCCAGCCAUGCUGCACCUGCCUUCAGAACAGGGCGCUCCUGAGACCCUCCAGCGCUGCCUGGAGGAGAAUCAAGAGCUCCGAGAUGCCAUCCGGCAGAGCAACCAGAUUCUGCGGGAGCGCUGCGAGGAGCUUCUGCAUUUCCAAGCCAGCCAGAGGGAGGAGAAGGAGUUCCUCAUGUGCAAGUUCCAGGAGGCCAGGAAACUGGUGGAGAGACUCGGCCUGGAGAAGCUCGAUCUGAAGAGGCAGAAGGAGCAGGCUCUGCGGGAGGUGGAGCACCUGAAGAGAUGCCAGCAGCAGAUGGCUGAGGACAAGGCCUCUGUGAAAGCCCAGGUGACGUCCUUGCUCGGGGAGCUGCAGGAGAGCCAGAGUCGCUUGGAGGCUGCCACUAAGGAAUGCCAGGCUCUGGAGGGUCGGGCCCGGGCGGCCAGCGAGCAGGCGCGGCAGCUGGAGAGUGAGCGCGAGGCGCUGCAGCAGCAGCACAGCGUGCAGGUGGACCAGCUGCGCAUGCAGGGCCAGAGCGUGGAGGCCGCGCUCCGCAUGGAGCGCCAGGCCGCCUCGGAGGAGAAGAGGAAGCUGGCCCAGUUGCAGGUGGCCUAUCACCAGCUCUUCCAAGAAUACGACAACCACAUCAAGAGCAGCGUGGUGGGCAGUGAGCGGAAGCGAGGAAUGCAGCUGGAAGAUCUCAAACAGCAGCUCCAGCAGGCCGAGGAGGCCCUGGUGGCCAAACAGGAGGUGAUCGAUAAGCUGAAGGAGGAGGCCGAGCAGCACAAGAUUGUGAUGGAGACCGUUCCGGUGCUGAAGGCCCAGGCGGAUAUCUACAAGGCGGACUUCCAGGCUGAGAGGCAGGCCCGGGAGAAGCUGGCCGAGAAGAAGGAGCUCCUGCAGGAGCAGCUGGAGCAGCUGCAGAGGGAGUACAGCAAACUGAAGGCCAGCUGUCAGGAGUCGGCCAGGAUCGAGGACAUGAGGAAGCGGCAUGUCGAGGUCUCCCAGGCCCCCUUGCCCCCCGCCCCUGCCUACCUCUCCUCUCCCCUGGCCCUGCCCAGCCAGAGGAGGAGCCCCCCCGAGGAGCCACCUGACUUCUGCUGUCCCAAGUGCCAGUAUCAGGCCCCUGAUAUGGACACCCUGCAGAUACAUGUCAUGGAGUGCAUUGAGUAGGGCCGGCCAGUGCAAGGCCACUGCCUGCCGAGGACGUGCCCGGGACCGUGCAGUCUGCGCUUUCCUCUCCCGCCUGCCUAGCCCAGGAUGAAGGGCUGGGUGGCCACAACUGGGAUGCCACCUGGAGCCCCACCCAGGAGCUGGCCGCGGCACCUUACGCUUCAGCUGUUGAUCCGCUGGUCCCCUCUUUUGGGGUAGAUGCGGCCCCGAUCAGGCCUGACUCGCUGCUCUUUUUGUUCCCUUCUGUCUGCUCGAACCACUUGCCUCGGGCUAAUCCCUCCCUCUUCCUCCACCCGGCACUGGGGAAGUCAAGAAUGGGGCCUGGGGCUCUCAGGGAGAACUGCUUCCCCUGGCAGAGCUGGGUGGCCGCUCUUCCUCCCACCGGACACCGACCCGCCCGCCGCUGUGCCCUGGGAGUGCUGCCCUCUUACCAUGCACACGGGUGCUCUCCUUUUGGGCUGCAUGCUAUUCCAUUUUGCAGCCAGACCGAUGUGUAUUUAACCAGUCACUAUUGAUGGACAUUUGGGUUGUUUCCCAUCUUUUUGUUACCAUAAAUAAUGGCAUAGUAAAAAUCCUUGUGCAUUA